UGCGUCCAGUGCUGCUUCCAGCGCUAGCCCCAGGGGCACGAAGGCUGGUGUAGGGAGGUGCGCCCCUCCGGGGGCCCGCCAGCCGUCAGACUCGAAGCUGUGGCUGUCAUUGCUUCUACAAUCAGUGCAUGUUCUUCGCUGACGUCAGUCGGAGCUGUCCUGGCACUAUAUAAGGCUGGCGACAGCCCCGGGACAGACCCUGUGUUCCCCAAGGCGUCUUCAGCCUGCCCCGAGGGACAGAGACUGGAGCUCAAUCUUGGACCGUACAGACGCUCGCCGACAACCUGGCCGGCGGCACCAUGAGGCAGGCGGGACGCGCAGCGCUGCUGGCCGCGCUGCUGCUCCUGGUACAGCUGUGCCCUGGGAGCAGCCAGAGGAGCCCCGAGGCGGCCGGGGUCCAGGACCCGAGUCUGCGCUGGAGCCCCGGGGCACGGAACCAGGGUGGCGGGGCCCGCGCGCUCCUCUUGCUGCUGGCGGAGCGCUUCCCGCGCCGCGCGGGGCCCGGCCGAUUGGGACUCGGGACGGCAGGCGAGCGGCCGCGGCGGGACAACCCUUCUCUGUCCAUUGACCUCACCUUUCACCUGCUGCGGACCCUGCUGGAGCUGGCGCGGACGCAGAGCCAGCGGGAGCGCGCCGAGCAGAACCGCAUCAUAUUCGACUCGGUGGGCAAGUGAUGGCCCGGUUUGGGGCUGCGAAAACGUUGACCCCUUUCCCCCACCCCAGAGUUGGGAUGCGGGGCAGAGCCACCAGGGCACUGUCUGCGUGACUAUUUUUUAAUAAAAGUACUGAAGACCC